GGGUGCCAUUCAGUGCCUGGGCUCCGGGAAAGUCGUGCUUUUACGGUUCCGGGUACUGGCUCCCACACCACUGCCUCGUGUGGGGUUGUUCGCCCGUGAAGGGGCAGGACAGGGUGCGCGCUGGUGGAGGUUGAAAUUGUUACAUUUUGGCCGGGCGCGGUGGCUCACGCCUGUAAUCCCAGCACUUUGGGAGGCCGAGGCAGGUGGAUCACGAGGUCAGGAGAUCGAGACCAUCCUGGCUAACACAGUGAAACCCCGUCUCUACUAAAAAAAUACAAAAAAUCAGCCGGGCGUGGUGACGGGCGCCUGUAGUCCCAGCUACUCAGGAGGCUGAGGCAGGAGGAUGGCGUGAACCCGGGAGGCGGAGCUUGCAGUGAGCCGAGAUCGCGCCAGUGCACUCCAGCCUGGGCGACAGAGCGAAACUACGUCUCAAAAAAAAAAAAAAAGAAAGAAAAGAAAUUGUUACAUUUUAUAUAUAUAGGAACAAUCCUGCACCAUGACUCAACAGCCACUUCGAGGAGUGACCAGCCUGCGUUUCAACCAAGACCAAAGCUGCUUUUGCUGCGCCAUGGAGACAGGUGUGCGCAUCUACAACGUGGAGCCCUUGAUGGAGAAGGGGCAUCUGGACCACGAGCAGGUGGGCAGCAUGGGCUUGGUGGAGAUGCUGCACCGCUCCAACCUUCUGGCCUUGGUGGGCGGUGGUAGUAGUCCCAAGUUCUCAGAGAUCUCAGCAGUGCUGAUCUGGGACGAUGCCCGGGAGGGCAAGGACUCCAAGGAGAAGCUGGUGCUGGAGUUCACCUUCACCAAGCCAGUGCUUUCUGUGCGCAUGCGCCAUGACAAGAUCGUGAUCGUGCUGAAGAACCGCAUCUAUGUGUACUCCUUCCCCGACAAUCCCCGAAAGCUGUUUGAGUUUGAUACCCGGGACAACCCCAAGGGGCUCUGUGACCUCUGCCCCAGCCUGGAGAAGCAACUGCUAGUGUUCCCGGGACACAAGUGUGGGAGUCUGCAACUUGUGGACCUGGCGAGCACAAAGCCUGGCACCUCGUCUGCUCCAUUCACGAUCAAUGCACAUCAGAGUGACAUAGCCUGUGUGUCUCUAAACCAGCCAGGCACUGUAGUGGCCUCAGCCUCCCAGAAGGGUACCCUUAUUCGCCUCUUUGACACACAAUCCAAGGAGAAACUGGUGGAGCUGCGCCGAGGCACUGACCCUGCCACCCUCUACUGCAUUAACUUCAGCCACGACUCCUCCUUCCUCUGCGCUUCCAGUGAUAAGGGUACUGUCCAUAUCUUUGCUCUCAAGGAUACCCGCCUCAACCGCCGCUCCGCGCUGGCUCGCGUGGGCAAGGUGGGGCCUAUGAUUGGGCAGUACGUGGACUCUCAGUGGAGCCUGGCGAGCUUCACUGUGCCUGCUGAGUCAGCUUGCAUCUGCGCCUUCGGUCGCAAUACUUCCAAGAACGUCAACUCUGUCAUUGCCAUCUGCGUAGAUGGGACCUUCCACAAAUAUGUCUUCACUCCUGAUGGAAACUGCAACAGAGAGGCUUUCGACGUGUACCUUGACAUCUGUGAUGAUGAUGACUUUUAAGGACCCUGGGGGCUGUGCUAGGGACCUGCAGUGGCAGAACUGCAGAGCUGAGCCUUGGCAGUGGGGCGUGCUUGGAAGCCACCAGCCAGCAAGCAUUAAUGGGGCUGGUGCCCACUUUCCACUCAGCAGAGCUAUGUCUAAAUAAAGAGCUCACUUCCCCCCAGCACUUCUUGAUGACUGUGUGCCCCAAGGGCCAGGCCAGAGACCCAGGAAGGCAGCGACCCCUUGGGAUCCCUAACCUGGAGGAAAUUGCCAGGGACCCAGAGGGAGUGCCCUAAUCCAACCUGGGGAUUUUUUAAAAGCUUCCUAGGAAGAGAUGAUCUCCGAUGUGAUGAAUACGAAUAAAAGGCCCUUAAUGGCA